GUUUAUAGCAUAGUCCACUGGGACUGCCGCUCUGACAAAGACUGUGUCACUACUUUGUGGAAUGUUAUUUUAGAACUUCCAGAAUGCCUCAGUAAAUCCUGACUGCCAUGUAACUGUGUACUGUGCUGCUGAGCUCUUAACAUGAAGCAGCAGCAGUGACCCUGGCGGGCCAGGCUGACGUGCGUGGGAACAGUGGGAGUGACCCUGGCUGGGAAGCAGGGAGGCCUGGAUAUUGUUUCUCCUGGCUCUGUGUCCUGCCAUUCUCAUCCCUGUGCUCAGAGCUCUCAAGCACCCACGAUGGCCUUCUCAGGCCGAGCGCGCCCCUGCAUUAUCCCAGAGAACGAAGAAAUCCCCCGAGCAGCCCUUAACACUGUCCACGAGGCCAAUGGGACCGAGGACGAGAGGGCUGUUUCCAAACUGCAGCGCAGGCACAGUGACGUGAAAGUCUACAAGGAGUUCUGUGACUUUUAUGCGAAAUUCAACAUGGCCAACGCCCUGGCCAGCGCCACUUGCGAGCGCUGCAAGGGCGGCUUUGCGCCCGCUGAGACGAUCGUGAACAGUAAUGGGGAGCUGUACCAUGAGCAGUGUUUCGUGUGCGCUCAGUGCUUCCAGCAGUUCCCAGAAGGACUCUUCUAUGAGUUUGAAGGAAGAAAGUACUGUGAACAUGACUUUCAGAUGCUCUUUGCCCCUUGCUGUCAUCAGUGUGGUGAAUUCAUCAUUGGCCGAGUUAUCAAAGCCAUGAAUAACAGCUGGCAUCCGGAGUGCUUCCGCUGUGACCUCUGCCAGGAAGUUCUGGCAGAUAUCGGGUUUGUCAAGAAUGCUGGGAGACACCUGUGUCGCCCCUGUCAUAAUCGUGAGAAAGCCAGAGGCCUUGGGAAAUACAUCUGCCAGAAAUGCCAUGCUAUCAUCGAUGAGCAGCCUCUGAUAUUCAAGAACGACCCCUACCAUCCAGACCAUUUCAACUGCGCCAACUGCGGGAAGGAUCUGACUGCCGAUGCACAGGAGCUGAAAGGGGAGCUAUACUGCCUGCCAUGCCAUGAUAAAAUGGGGGUCCCCAUCUGUGGCGCUUGCCGACGGCCCAUCGAAGGGCGUGUGGUGAACGCCAUGGGCAAGCAGUGGCAUGUGGAGCAUUUUGUUUGUGCCAAGUGUGAGAAACCCUUUCUUGGACAUCGCCAUUAUGAGAGGAAAGGCCUGGCGUAUUGUGAAACUCACUAUAACCAGCUAUUUGGUGAUGUUUGCUUCCACUGCAAUCGUGUUAUAGAAGGUGAUGUGGUCUCUGCUCUUAAUAAGGCCUGGUGCGUGAACUGCUUUGCCUGUUCUACCUGCAACACUAAAUUAACACUCAAACCUUCUGCCAGAAAGUGGGCCUGCUGUGCACGCUUCAGGGUAAGCUGCAGCCCCAGGACUGGACAUUGUUGGACGAACUGCUGCAGGGCCUGCAAACACUGCUGCUCAUGAUUUUGUGGCAGGCUUCCCGUGGCCUCUUCCUGCACUACCAUGUGGAGGCCCUAACCCUGCGUCGCAUCAGUAGCUUCCGCCAGUACAAGUAUGACCUGGUGGCAGCGGGCAAGGCUUUGGAGGGCAUGUUCUGCAAGCUCAACCACCUCCUGGAACACCCGCACCAGCUGUUCUUCCUCUACCUGCUCCCCACUCUGUCCCGCUUCGUCUCCAUCGGCCUCUACAUGCCCGCCACCAGCUUCUUGCUCCUGGUCCUUGGUUUCAAGGCUCUGCAACUGUGGAUGCAGCUGCAUGAGGCCGGAGUGGGCCUUGAGGAGCUCAGGGGGGUCCCUGACCCUAGUGUCCCCGCUCCCCCAGCACAGGAUGGUAAGCACACAGGUCCCAGACAGGGGCUGGAUGGCUCUGAAGCUGGUAGCCCUGAUCUACCUAAUACUGCAGCUGGGCUGCAUCGCCCUCACCAACUUCUGACUGGACUUCCUGCUGGCCGCCACUAUGGUGCUGCCGCUGUGCUCGCCGAGCCUUUGGGCCCUGGACCCUCUGUGCUGCCCUGCUGGUGUUGACAAGCCCAGCAGCCACGCUCCUUGGCAGCCCAUUCCUGUGGCGGGAGCUGCAGGAGGCACCACUGUCACUGGCCAAGGGCUGGCAGCUCUUCCUGGCAGCACUGGCCCAGGGUGCGCUGGAGCACCACACCUAAGGCGCCCUGCUCUUCCCACUGCUGUCCCUGGGCCUCUGCCCUUGCUGACUACUUUUCUGGAAUGUGCUCUUCUGGAAGUGAGAUCUGCCUGUCCGGGGCACCAGGCUGGGACAGAGACUCCCCAAGGACCCCAUUCUGCCUCCUUCUGGGGAAAUAAACAAGUGCCUGUUUCAGCUGCUUUAAAAAAAAAUAGAAAAAAAAAAUGCCCUGGAAAAUACUGUGUUAGCAAAAAGAUUUAAAGAUUGGUAUAAUUCUGAUUUAAAUGUUUUAUUUAGCACAAAAUCAAACAUUGCAUAGGAACAAAAUUUUCUGAGACAAAAUGGCUGGGUUUAAAUGGGUUUAAAUGUCUAAAAAAUACUUAGCUAACAGUGUGGUUAAAUUUUUACUUAUUUUAUUUAUUUUUGAGAUGGAGUUUCAUUCUUGUUGCCCAGGCUGGAGUGCAGUGGUGCGAUCUCAGCUCACCGCAACCUCCACCUCCAAGGUUCAAGUGAUUUUCCUGUCUCAGCCUCCUGAGUAGCUGGGAUUAGAGGCGUACACCACCACACCCAGCUAAUUUUUGUAUUUUCAGUAGAGAUGGGGUUCGCCAUGUUGACCAGGCUGGCCUCGAACUCCUGACCUCAGGUGAUCCACCAUUCUCAGCCUCCCGAAGUGCUGGAAUUACAGGCGUGGGCCACUGCCCCCGGUCAAGUGUUUUUCUUUUUUUCUUUUGAGAUGGAGUCUCACUCUGUUGCCCAGGCUGGAGUGCAGUGGCACGAUCGAGGGUCACUGCAACCUCCGCCUCCUGGGCUUAAGCAAUUCUCCUGCCUCAGCCUCCUGAGUAGCUUGGAAUACGGGCACCCACCACCCCACCUGGCUAAUUUUUUGUAUUUUUAGUAGAGAUGGGGUUUCACCAUGUUGGCCAAGCUUGUCUUGAACUCCUGACCUCAAGUGAUCCGCCUGCUUUGGCCUCUCAAAUUGCUGCGAUUACAGGCGUGAGACACCGCGCCCGGCCCCGGCCAAGUUUUUAAGCAGAUACAUUAGUUACAUGUGCUGAAAUAUCAGAUGACUCCCCCAGAUUUCACUGACUUCACAUUAUAUUUUGGGCCCACCAGAAGUUGCUGGCUGGGCGUUCAGGGUAGAGGCUGCUUUCCUCUGCGUGGGCAUGCAGGAACCCAGAAUCUUUCCAUCAGGUGCCUCCGUCAUCUCUGGGACCUCCUCCCACCUGCAUCUAUCGGUAGAAGGGGAGAGUGUGAGAAAGGCAUUGGAGGCUUUUGUGGGCCAGCUCUGGAAGUGGCUCACCUUAGUCCAUUGCCUCCCUUUGGCAAAAGCUGGUCAUAGGACUACACCUAACAUAAGGGGACUAUGAACUAGAGCUUUUAUUUAUUUGUUUGUUUGUUUGUUUGUUUAGGCCCCAUGGGGGCUGUGAACUGGAGCUUCUAUUUAUUUAUUUAUUGUUUAGGCACCAUGGCCUACACUCCUUUAUUAGAGUGAGGGUCCCGAGGACCAGCCCCCAUAUAUGAUGGGUCCACUUGAGCCUCCUUAGGAGCCCCAUGAGGGAGUGAUGGCUUGGGUAGGGAGCCAGGGACCUUGCCCAGCCCGACACUGGAGCAGGAGAGCGGCCUCAGUCCCCACCCCAACCCCAGAAGAGGGCGGGGCGAGAACCGGAGUCAAAUCUUGGGCCGGGUCCAAGGGCCUGAGCGCCUGGUUUAGGCCGGAAAUGGUCUAGUUCUCAGAGGUGGUCCGAUCCCUAACCAGUCCCAGGCCCAGCCCCAGCCCAGCACCACCUGGAAGGUUCAAGUACAUGGAGGAGAGGAGUAAGGCGGACUUGGGCGUAUGGAGAAAGGGGUGAAGGGAGAAAGAGGACUUGCGCUCAGGAGGGAGCGUGGCCUACUGGUGGGAAAGCAGGCGUGGCCGCCUGUGCGGGAGGUUGCGGAUCCACAGUGGGCGAGACCAGGCCCCAGCCCCAUCAGGGCGCGGGGUGCGCAGCCAGGUGGUGCUCCAGCAGCGCCCAGUGAGAGGAGACCUUGCGGUAGACGGGGGAAGGGCGCGCGCUCUGGCCGCUGAGUGCGCAUGUGCAUAUUGAGCGAACUCUUCUGCGGGAAGGGCUUGGCGUAGACCGCGCACUGGAAGGCGUGCGCGCAGGUGUGCGUGACCAUGUGCUUGAAACGGCAGUAGCGCAGCGAGAAGGAUCGCCAUCACACGGCGCACUGGUGCGGCUUCUCCCCCGAGUGGAUGAACAUGUGCUUGGUGUCGUUUUUCCUUGAGCUGAACGUCUUGCAACAGUGGCCGCACGCAUAGGCAAGUGGCUCGGCACCAGGAGUGCGAGCAGUGGUGCCUGAGGGGGCCGUGGUGGGAGCAGCAGAGGGAGCCGGGGCCUCCCGCAGCUGAGUGCCGGGGGCUGCCUCGGGCUGGAGUGUGGGGUAGAAGGCGGGUGGGGGCGCAGGGGCUGGCACGGAUGGUGCUGAAGGGGGUGGUGCGGGUGGUUCGGGAGCACCCAAGUGAAAGGGGAAGAGUGCGACAGGCGGCCCUGGGGUCUUCACGCCAGGCGGGCGGGGUCCAGCCAGUAUGCAGUCGGGCUGGACAGGGGUCUCGGUGGGACAGCCUUCGGGGACAGCGCCAUCCUUGUCGUGCCAAGCGGUUACAUAGCUGUCUGGAAAUACGUCCUCAGCUGCCCCAGAUCCCGGAAGAAAAUCUCUCCCACACCACUGUAGUCAGAGAGGCCAGUGGGUGCAUGGAACUCCUCGCACGCGCUGUCAGCAGCAGCAGUGAGGAAGCCGGCAGCACAGUCUGGGAAGGAAGGAGGUGCUUGGCUCUCUCCCGGGCCGCCACCUUCGCCGUCCUCGCCAUCGGUCUCAUCGUCAGUUUCCUCGUCAUCGUUGUCACCUCGGUCGUCAGGGGCCGCGGACAGUGAGGGGUAGGCACCAAGCCCCUCGGCUUUGGCAGGUGUCGGGGGCGCAGGCAGCUGCAAACUCGCGGGCCGGCGCUGCUUACCGCUGUGCGCGGCACCGGGGUGCCCCGGGGGUGCGCAGCCAGCAGGUGGCGCAGGCGGUGACGCAGCUGCUCAGGUGCGAGUGGCGGGGGCACAGGGGUGGGCAGGGGCGCGGGUGCAGAGGUGCUCGCGGGUGCAGAGGAGCGCGUGCGAUAAUCUGCGUGCAUUCGUCGAUAACUGUCUAUGCGAAGCACCGACGCAGCCAUGAGUACCUGCGGGGCUUCACUCUGUGCCACAACGAGCGAACCGCUGUACAGGAGCUCGACUAGCUGUCGCACCGUCUGCACAGGCACCACCGAAGGCACACGGAUCUCAGAGGGGCCGAGCAGCAGCUUGUCUUGGAAGGAGGGCGAGCCGAUUGCCAGCCCGCAGCGGUGCGCACGCAGCGAAGCUUCAUGAAUGCACACAGUCACGUCGCAGAAGUGCCCACCCAGCUUCUGCCCAUUGAGGGUCUCAAGCAGAGAGCGUGAGAAGUUCUGCAGAUGUAUGUGGCGCACAGCCUCUACAGCCGCCGACUCCGACUCCUCUUCAGGCACCAGGCCUGGCCGUGGCCGCCUUCUCACCGACUCCAAGGCAGCACUUCCGGGCGCUUCUCUUUAUUUUUAUACAGUUUUAUUGAGAUAUAAUUUACAUGCUAUCCAGCCCAUCUAUUUCAAGUGUACCAUGCAAGGGGUUUGUAUAUAUUCACAGAGUUGUGUAUCCAUCACCAUCGUUUUAGAACAUUCAUCACUCCAGAAGAAACUACUACCCAUCAGCAGCCACUGCCCAUUUCCCUGAUCUGCCCCGCCCUAGGAAAUCCGUAAUCACUUUCAGUCUAUGGAUUUGCCUAUUCUAGACCAUUCAUAUAAAUGAAGUCACACAACACUGGGUCUUAUGUGACUGGCUUCUAUCAAAGUUUGCAAGGUUCAUUUAUGUUCAUGGUAUGUAUCAGUAGCUUGUUACUUUUUAUGUUUGACUUCUAUUCUGUUACUUACCUACACCGUAUUUUAUCUAUCUCUUCUGCAGUUUAUGGGAUUUAGGUCGUUUCCACGUUUUGGCUGUUCUAAAUAAUGCUGCUCUGAGCGUUCACAUACAAGCUUUUCACAUGAUUUCAUUUCUCCAGAUCUAGGAGUGCAAUUGCUAUAUUAUAUGGCAACCCCGUGUUUCACUUUUUGACAAAGUGCCAGACUGCUUUUCAAAGGACAGCAUCAUUUUAUAUUCCUGCCAGCAAUGUCGAGGGGUCCAGUUUCCACACAUUCUCACAAACACUUAUUGUUAUCUGUCUCUCUAGUUAUUGCCUUCCUGAUGGAUGUGGAGUGCUUUCUCAUUGGUUUUGAUUUGCAUUGUUUAAAUGAGUUAUAAGAUUGAGCAUGUUUUCAUGUUUAUUGGCUGCUUGUAUAUCUUCUUUGGAGAAAUGUCUAUUCAGAUUGUCUCCCCAUUUUAAAAUCGUGUUAUUUUCUUUUUUACUAUUGACUUGUGAAUGUUCAAACAUGUAUAUAUAUAUAUAUAUAUAUAUAUAUAUAUAUAUAUAUAUAUAUAUAUAUAUUUUUUUUUUUUUUUUUUUUUUUUUUUUUUUUUUGAGACGGAGUCUUACUCUGUUGCCAGGCUGGAGUGCAGUGGCACGAUCUUGGCUCACUGCAAUCUCUGCGUCACGGGUUUAAGUGAUUCUCCUGCCUCAGCCUCCUGAGUAGCUGGGACUACAGGCAUGCACCACCACACCCGGCUAAUUUUUGUAUUUUUAGUAGAGACGGGGUUUCACCAUGUUGGCCAGGAUGGUCUCAAUCUCCUGACCUCGUAAUCCACCCACGUUGUUCUCCCAAAGUGCUGGGAUUACAAGGUGUGAGCCACCGCGCCCGGCCCAAACAUAUUCUUAUACAAUUCUCUUCUUAGAUAUAGGGUUUGCAAACAUUUUAUCUCACAUUGUAAUUAUUUUUUCAUUUUCUUGAAAGUCUACUUUGAUACAGGAAUAUUUGUGAAUUUUAUAAAGUACAGCUUAUCUAUAUUUUCUAUUAUACUUGUGGUUUUGGUAUGAUAUCCAUAAAAUCAUUGCCUAACCCAAGGUCACAAAGCCUCAGUCCCAUAUUUUCUCCUACGUGUACUAAACUUUUGGCUUUUAUAUUUAGGUCUUUGAUCCAUUUAGGGUUAACUUUUAUAAAUGGUGUGAGGGAGGGGACUAACUUCAGUCUGUACAUGUGAACAUCAAUCUGUCCCAGGACAUUUUUGAAAAGACUAUUCACUCCCCAUUGAAUUGCCUUGUCUCCCUUGUCAAAGUCACAACAAUUACUGUCCUCAUUUUUGUAUCUGGUCACAUGUUCCUAGUUAGUAACUAUAACUACCCUCUUCUACUACGCAUUCUGUAUUCCCUUAGCUUUCAGCAAGCAACUCAGUUGGUCUUGAUUCUUUAUAUGGGGCAAUGACCCAAACUUUCCUUCCUGAAGGAAUUGGGCCAUUGGCAGCUGUGCCCGAAUUGGGUUGUUGUAGUUUUCCAUUAAAUUAAUCACAGGGCAUGGUAGUAGGUAGCACUGAAGACACCCUAGGAGAUCCCAUGUAUUCCAGAAGUAUUAUUUCUUAGUUCUGUGGAGUAGAAGCAAUUAACCCUUGGUAGUCAGGAUCAACCACCUCUGCCAGCACGGUAACUCCCUUCUUUGCCUGUCUAUUCAGAGGCAUGAGGAGCUCAGAGUGGACAGGGACUAUCUUAACUUCCAGUUCAGUAGAAUCAUUUCUUUGUAUCGUGGGGGAUGCAUUCCUCCUUUUGGGACCAAGACUUCUAGACCAGCAGAGCAUAAGAUUGAGGGACAGGAAAUGAAAAUUUUGCUGGUGUGUCACUAGGGGUAAUAGUGAUGAUGAGAACCAAUUGGUGUGGGAGACCAUGAGGUGGAUAAGGCACUCUGUAAGUCCAGACAGUAGUGUGAUUUUUAUGAAGUACAAUUUAUCAGUGGUGAUAGGAACAUUGAGGGUAGGAGGGGAAAUUCUCAUACAUAGUGUCUGUUUCAGUGAGAACAAGACACUGCCUCUUCUAUGAUGGAGGUGGUUCAGAGUCACAGCCAGGUUACCUUGGGAGUGGAAGUCCAUGUUGCAGAGCCCAGGCAUCACCUCCACCCCUGCCACCAUGGCCACUGUAUUCAUGAGCCCAUUGAGCAAUGACAGGGGUGGCUGGGGAAAGAGGCUGAGUGGUGUCCACAGAACAGGUCAUCCUAUCUGCUUGAUUAUUGAAAUCCUUCUCUGCCAAGGCCACCCUUUGGAGAGCAUUUACAUAGCACUCAAUGCACUCUUGCUUUUGGUUUACUCUUUUACUAGGUGAAACCAGUCCUAGUGGCUCAUAACUGGGUUUUCCUAUCAUACUUGUCCUCAGUCCGUAGGUGAAACAACAAAUGUAGGGAUGCUGAAAGUUGCUGAGUAUGUGUCUAUUCCAACCACAGGGUGGGUUCAGGGACACAUUGGAUCCACUGUGAAACAGACAUGAGCUCACACUCCAUCCACCAGCUAACCUCCAUAAGUCCCUACUCUGGUGGACCACAGUGAUGUUUUUGGUCUCUGGGAAUUCCUGUCAAAUCAGAGCCAGUGUCCAGAAUUCCCCAAAUAUCUGAGAAUUUUCUUUUCUCUAAGUCACAGUCAUCCUGGUAGAAGGCUGUAGGUCCCUUUGGGGAAGACUGGGAAAAAGAUUAACUAUGUAAGUUUUUGGCAAUGUAGCAGCGUACUUCCCCAAGAUCACCCAGCCUCCCCUUCACUUAGGGGUUGUGGGCCUGUGAACUGGCUCAAGUCUGGGAAUUGAUUGAGGGUUUAGAUCUGUGUUUCAUUAAUUUGAGUUAGUCUUUUAUUCAGUUGACCUAGAAUUCUUCAUUUUUUAAAAAACAACUAAGACUUUGGUACAGCCCAUUAGCUCUCCCUGUGGAUACCAUGGACUACACAAUGCCAUGGGUUUCUGUGAGUCAAACCAUUCUGACUGCUGCUUUGACACUGCUUUCCACUGUAGUGACCACACCCACCUCAUCUUUGGUGAUUAAGGACAGCCCAUGUUCCCUGCCACCCCAGGAUUCAAUUAUCCUCAUUUUAUUUAAAGAUCCCAGUCCAGUGGCUGCAGUUUCUGCUGUAACAUUUUGCCUACUGAGAGCACGAGCUCAAAGCUCUUCCAGGAUACUGGGCUCCUCUCACAAUAUUCUUUCUCAUGAUCGUUGUGAGAAGUAUGUUCUGUAGACCCUCCAGUGUGAGUGAGCAGGUCUGACAUAAUAAAUCCAGUCUCCCUGAGUUUUUGCAUACCUUCCUAUACACAUAAACCAAGGAAGUUGUGACAUCUCAACUUUAUGUACUUUAGGUAAACUCUGAUUCUGUUUCAGCCAACCAGCCAAGUAACAAAACAAAUAAGCAAACAGCCAACCAAUCAACCAACAAGCAAGCAAGCAACAAACCAACCAAACAAGCAAGCAAGCAAGCAAGCAACCAACCAACCAACCAAGUAACCGAUCAAACCAACCCUUGGAGCCCUUUCUAAAACUUUGACCUACAACCCUGAAUCCAGAAUCUCUGUUUAGUGGGCCAACAUUAAUAAAUUUAGCCUACUCCAACUUUGUGUUACUUCCACCAUGGUGCCACACACUUAAUAUCCAUUCCCACAUAUAUUCUCCAGAUUUCUUUCUGUAUAAAUUGUGUGUGUGUGUGUGUGUGUGUGUGUAGAAAGAGAGCAUCAACUGAAAAAUCACACAAUUUUAUAAAUUUAGAAAAGAGAGCUUUAUUUCUUAUAAAGGUUUGCAGCCUGCAAGGUGGCCAUUAUGACAGGCUGGGAAGUGUGGCCUACAGCCAAGGCUAGAGGCAGGCCCUUCCAGGGAGGGAAGGAGAGGACAGGAAUUUGAGCUGAAUGAGUUGACUACAUAUACAUACUCAAUAGGAUAUCAGAGGAGCUAUAUCAUUUUAUGAGAAUACUCAUAAAAGAGGUCCUAACACAUGCAUAUUGAAUAAACAUGCAUGUUCAUUCUGGGGUGGAGACUUGACAUUUAAAUGUGUUAUAAUUAGGCCCUACACAUCAAAAAGUGAAGCAGGGAAUGAAGGUACUCAGCCUCUGUAAAGGCACAGCCUCUAAAACUGGCCAGAACCAGUCCAUGGAGGAUGGUCUCUUAUCAGGAGAAAGUUACUGAAAUCAGUCCCUUGUCCAGUGAAAGCUGUCGUUAAGGUCGGUGGGGCAGGAGAUCAGUUACUCAGUGUCUGUGAACUGGGUGAGUUGUAAUUGUUUUAAUCUUGCUUCUCUCAUAGCCAGUGCUUGCUUGGCUGCUAGAGAAAAAUAAAAACUAUGUGGUAGUUAGAAUCUAGUUUAUUCUUUAAGAGUAGGGUACAAGACUUAACCCUUGCCUGGCAUGGCCCUAGGUCCUGUUUAUAAUUUGGGGUCUUAUUGCCACAAAGAGUCUGUUCUGUCAGUCUCAUGAUCUCUAUUUUAACGUUAAUGCUGUUCAGUUGUUGGGUCUAAACCAUAAGAGGGAGAGAGGUACAGGGAGUUAUGUCUGACCUCCUGUCCUGUCAUGGCCAAGAACUGAAUUUUAAGAUUUAUUUGAGGUUCCGUUGGCCAACAGGGGGUCUGUUAAGUCGGGUGGGGGGCUUAGGGUUUCAUUUUUAGUUCUCAAGGGAGAUAAAAUAAUUUAAUCAAUUGGCCCCUGUGACUAUUGGACUAACAUGGCUAUGAUCUGUCAGACAGACUUCAGGCUGGCACCCAGGCAAAAUUCUAUACUGUAGUAAAUGCAUCAUGCACAUUUGUAACAACAUGUACAUAACAAUGUCACAAAAUACUUUCACGGUGACACCUAGAUUAGUGUUUUAUUGAAUAGCUGAUGAUAUAAACUGGCUCAUUUGAUGCCAAGACUGACCAUCACCACCAUACCAAGGUCAUCACUGAUCAGAGGCCUAACCCAAGGAGGGGGUCAUGUGCAGACCCAGCUGUGGGGAGGAAAGAUGCUGCAGAGGAGACGGAUGCCCACAGAGGCCCCUGAGUGGAUACAAUGCUCACUAAGUGGUAAGUAUAGACUCAACGUAGGCUGUCAGGUCUCCCCCUGUGCAAAUGGGACAUCCACUUGAGAGUCAAGGGUCUGUUUGGGUGGCAGGGAUAGCCACUUCUGAAGGUAGAAAGAAAAAUAAGCCACCAAAUUGGUAUCUUUCUGUGAAAUGGACAUCGUGCUUAGAGUCUCCAUUUUCCCCACAACCUGGAGGAAUAAGUAUUGUCAUCUGCAUUUUAUAGCUGAGGAAUCUGACUCAACAAAAUUAAAUUACUCACCUAAGCAAUUAGCAAUUAACCAAGUCUUUCUGAUUCAGAAACCCAGCUGUUGCCUGUUCAUAUCCAGCCCCUGUAUUGGGAUCAAGAUCUGCCCUAUUCUCAGUGCAGCAAGAUCCAGGCAGAUCACACUGGACUCCCAGCACUGAAUCUGGCUCAAGGGGACAUGAAAUUUGACUGGGUCAUGGGACUCAGGAGCAUCACUCUCAAAAAUAGCAGUACAGGAAGAGGCGAUGGCCCUAAACAGCAUUUGCAGGCAGAUCCCAUGUUAAUCAUAAGGGCCAGGACUCUCUCACUGUCUGUCUCUCUCUCUGUCUCUCCUCUAGGGCUGACCCCACAUUGGACACCGCUGCAUCCAUGUCCAUCACACAACACAGCUGCCGUUUCUUCUGCCUGCUUAUGGGAAAGUCCCCUCUUCUCCUCCGUUUUCUUCUCUUCCUGCCCUAUCACACCGUGCACUUCUCCCUUUCCUUAAAGAACCACCAUCAACUUUAGGAGGAGGGAAAGGGGUGGCUCUGGCAGGAAAAGCCAGAAUCCCCUCUAGCCAGCAGAGAGAGAGAGGAAUGGCUGCAUGUUUUCUCCCCCAGUCCAAGGCACUGGGUCUUGGCUGGGUUGAAGGUUCCAAGCUGCUCUCCUGCUGUGUCGGUGAGUUCUGGUCAACCUGCAACCUCCUGAUAUGGCCAUUGCAGUUCAUCGAGUCUUCAGGGACUCCCCAUGGCCUGGAGUACUUUGCCUUGCUUACACGGGAGAGGAGAAUGGAUUUAUAGAGAACAUCAUCUAAAUCCAACUUGACCAUUGUGUGGCCACACUUGCUAGAUUGCUAUAGUCUAAAUCUAGCAUUGUAGAAAGACGGGGGAGCUUGGAGCUGCACAAACCCAGGUCUGGAACUGGCUCCUUACCUUGGAAGGUGAAUGAUCCUGCCAGGACUCUUAGCCUCCCUGGGUCUCAAUUUCUUUAUCUGUUUCAUGGGAAUGAGGAUCUCUGCUGGGUGGUUGGGUGAUGUGGGGGCUGUGUGAAAACAGCUUGUCAAUACAAGCCAAAAUAGAAAUAUUUCUCCACAGAGUAUGAAGGUCAAAUGAGAGAAUACAUUUAAAUUAAAUGGAAAAUUAAAAUGGUAAAAAAUGCAAAGCUGUAUUGAAAGUUCCGAGCUUCUCUAUAAGGAGCUUUUUGACUAUGUAAGAAUCCUGUACUCGUUCCCCCUAAAUAUAAAAAAAAGUUGAAGGAGGCAGAAGGGAGAGUGAUGCACGAUGGGCAAGGACUUCACCUGCUGUUGCUGGCUUUGAGGAUGGAGGAAGGAGGCCACAAACCUAGAAGCUGGAGCCCCUAGAAGCUAGAAAAGGCAGGGACCCGAUUCUUUCCUUGAGCCUCCAGAAGGGACACAGCCCCGCCAGCACCUUGACUUUAGCCUGGUGAGAUCCUCUUAGGACUUUUGGCAAUCAGAACUAUAAGACAGAAAUGGAAGCCACUGAGUCUGUAGCUGUUUGUUGCAGCAGCAAUAGAAAACUAAUGCAGGGCCCAAGAAAUCACUGGUGAUGAGAUCGGGAAAGUGGGCUCAGGAGGUCUGGAUCUGUGAUGAGAUGGGGAAAGUGGGCUCAAGAGGUCUGGAUCUGUGGUGAGAUGGGGGAAGUGGGCUCAGGAGGUCUGGAUCUGUGAUGAGAUGGGGAAAGUGGGCUCAGGAGGUCUGGAUCUGUGAUGAGAUGGGGAAAGUGGGCUCAGGAGGUCUGGAUCUGUGAUGAGAUGGGGGAAGUGGGCUCAGGAGGUCUGGAUCUGUGAUGAGAUGGGGGAAGUGGGCUCAGGAGGUCUGGAUCUGUGAUGAGAUGGGGGAAGUGGGCUCAGGAGGUCUGGAUCUGUGAUGAGAUGGGGAAAGUGGGCUCAGGAGGUCUGGAUCUGUGAUGAGAUGGGGGAAGUGGGCUCAGGAGGUCUGGAUCUGUGAUGAGAUGGGGAAAGUGGGCUCAGGAGGUCUGGAUCUGUGAUGAGAUCGGGAAAGUGGGCUCAAGAGGUCUGGAUCUGUGGUGAGAUGGGGGAAGUGGGCUCAGGAGGUCUGGAUCUGUGAUGAGAUGGGGAAAGUGGGCUCAGGAGGUCUGGAUCUGUGAUGAGAUGGGGAAAGUGGGCUCAGGAGGUCUGGAUCUGGGGUGGGGAUCUGGAGUGGAAGGGGAAUUCAUUUGUUCAUUGUCUAUCCUUUUGUAUUGAUUGAAUUUUUUAUAUAUAUAUGUGAAUUUUCACAAUAAAAUUUUUUUCCAAAAUAAAAUAAACAAAAGGGGCUUUUUGCAACCCAAUUCCUAUCUAUGUCUGAGUCCACUUGUAUUGCAUGGGUCUUUCUGCUAACGUCCUUAUAUUUGGGUGACAAUCUGAAUGUCAGCGACCAAUCAGAGCAGAGGCAGACUUUGGAGUGGGCAGGGCAUCCUGAGGGCCCUGAUUCCUGCCAUGAGACGUAACCCUUUAGGUGCCAGACCAUGGGGAGGUCCAGGGGUUGCAGGGGAGGGCUGUGCAUCUGCAAUGGCUCUCAGGGGGGCUCCCGGUGGUGGCAAUCGGUGAAUCUGCACAGUGGUGCUUCAAUAUUAUCACAACCCUGCUGUCUCUCAUGCUCUCAAAAAGCGUUUCUCUUACCUGUGACAGACUUCCUAUACCUAACAGCUUGCAAAAAUGUUUCAGGUUAAUGAGAAUAAUCUCUUGGAGCCAUACCUCCCUGCUUGGGGUCUCAGUUUCCCCAGCUGUCUCCAGACAAGUUAGGCUAGAAGGCCCCUGAGCCUCAGCCCCUCUAUCCCCCUCCUGUCACCCAGACCUGAUCUGGGUCUUGCACCCUGGGUGCAGCAUGACAGGGGUGGGCAGGGGCUGGCUCUGGGCCAGAGGACCCUUUCUGAUGGACUUCAGCUGUUGGCCUUCCAGGGGAGACUGAUCAACCUCACAAGAGUCAUAAGGUGAGUAGCGGUGGGCAAAUCCAUCCCCCUCAUCUUAGAUUUAUGGGGAUACAGAGAGAAAGAGGAGACACUCCAGGAAGACGUGCAGGUGGGAGUACCAGGUUGAAACCAAGGACACCUUCCUGGAGGAGUUGCUGUUUGAGCCAGCUCUGAGAACAGGUGGGGACAGGACUGGAGAGGAGGAGGGGGUGCCCUAUGAGCAAAGACUGGCCACCACCCCAUCUAACACCCCCACAGGGCCCCUGUGGCAUCCCUGUCCAGUCCCUGUCACCACCCACUUUUUCCCUCUGGACCCAGGAAUUCAAAGUAAGCAAGGAGGUCCGCUGCUCCAGUUGGCUGCAAAUAAUUACAACCUUGAGCCCAAGCAGCACUUUGGGUCCUGGUUUGGGACGAUGAAGCAGCUCGGUGAGACUGAGAGGUAAGGCCAGGGCAGGAAUUGGGACACUAGGAUUGAACUCUCCCUGGGGGCCAGCCUCAGAAAGCCUGUGGCCAUGGCCUCUUGGCCAACAUCAGAUCCUGUGGUCUGGCAAUGCCUGGGGUACCCAGACCUCACUCUGCACAGGCCCUGGGAGGGGGCCCUGGUGAGAUUCCUGGCAGCCUCACAGCCACUCUUCUGUCCAUAGCUACAACCUGUCAUGCCAGCUGGAGGCUCCAUCCCAGUUGGCUGGGAGCACAAAGGCCAGGAAGGUAGACAUCACCCACCACAGGGGCCAGUCGGGGCCUGAACCAGGGCGGGCAGAGAUUGGCUGCCUUGGGCUAUGGGUGGGCUCAGGGAGUCAGAGAGCAAGGGACUAGCCUCCCAUCCUACUGCUGACCAGCCCUGUGACUGGGGAGAGUCACCUUACUUCUCUGGGCCUCAGUUUCCCCCUCUGUGGAGUGACACUAAAUGCUCUCUCUGGAGACUGGGAUCAAUGGGGCACUGGUGAUUGACCAGGCACUCAGCACAUGCCUGGAGCACACAGUGCAGGGCUGUGGUGGGGAGGUGGCCUGGGUCCCUGGGGAGGCACCCAUGUGUGCCUGCCCUUCCGACCAGCCACCAGGCCCUCAGGGCAGAGCCCACUACCAGCAGCAGCUCACACCCCGAGACCAGCUCAGAGGCGGCCCCUACCUCAGCAGCAGGGACAUCACGGACACUUUGAGCUGGUACUAGGGCAGCUUCUCCGGCUCCCACCUGGAGAGGGGUCCCAGCUGAGUCCCACUCACGUGAAGUCUCAUGCCCCUGAAAGUGCCAUUCACCACUGGCCAGGCUCAUGAGGCCACAUGAGGGGGGGGGUGUCACUGGGGAGGAGAUAUGGGGGGAACAGAGGGGUGGUUGAAUUUUUGUAUAAUAGGCAGUGCAAGUGUUUACCGUUUGGGAGGGGAAAGGUUUGUUAUUAUUAGCAGUGCUACACUUGAAUAUUAUACUAAAAUCCAGUUUCUCUAUAACCUGGGAGUUGCUCUUUUGUUCUUUCUUUUCCUGUCUUAAUUAAAAUGAGAUGCAGGUUCUCACGGUCCACAGUCGAUUAAGAAAUCUUGCAGGGCCAUCAGUUAUGUCUUGGAGAGCAGGGUUUCAGUACCAUCAGCCUGGCAAGGAGCUGGGCCUGCCCCUCAGAGCUCCCGGGACUGCGAGAUUUGGCACAUUCACAGGGCACUGUCACAGCCUCUGAAACGCUGUCUUUAAAGACAUCUGCAGGCUGGACGCGGUGGCUCACUCCUGUAAUCCCAGCACUUUGAGAGGCAGAAGCAGGUGGCUCACUUGAGGUCAGGAGUUUGAGACCAACAUGGCCAACAUGGCAAAACCCCAUCUCUACUAAAAAUACAAAAAUCAGCCAGGUGUGGUGGCAGGUGCCUGUAAUUCCAGCUACUUGGGAGGCUGAGGUAGGAGAAUUGCUUGAACCCAGGAGGCGGAGGUUGCAGUGAGCAGAGAUCGCACUACUGCACUCCAGUCUGGGCAACAAGAGCAAAACUUCAUCUCAAAAUAAAAAAAAUAAAAAACAUAAAAAAGACAUUUGCAAGGACCAUGUCCUCACCCAGAAUGGUGCCUGCCUUUCUACAGUUUUUCAGGAAGAGGAAACAUUUUCUGCUUCUCUCGCUGAGGUUUUUUUUAACCACCCAUUAGGAACCUAUAGAUUUCAGGAUCAAACACUGGGAUUCCCUCAGCACUAAAGGAGGAAAAUUGCAAACAGAGCUGAAAGUGCAAUGUGGAAAGGUCAGGCUGAGGAAGGUUCUUAGCCAGUAGACCAAUGGCAGGAAGGACACUGCCUCCUCAGUCUCCCACUAGGGAACUUGUGGUUCUUGUCCCCUGACCUCAGAAUUCCUUGUCAUGUUUGUUUUGUCUCCAAGGGAAGGGUUUGCAUUACAGAAUUUAAGGCUAGAGUGGGCCUCGUGCAGUUAACAUUAACCCUCUCUCUCCUUUGCUGGCUGAGGUGAAGUCUGGGACCAUAUAGUUCUGACGUCCACUCUCUCGGGGGAUCACCAGUUCACCCACCUCACCUGGCAAGCUGGGCCCUAGUUUGGCGACAGGCAUCUUCCACCCACCUGGGAGGCAGGGUUCAACACUCUGCCUCUGACCUUGUUUCCUUCCUCUGCCACCUGCUUAGGCAGCCAGAAGGGGUUGUCUAGCCAGCCUGGGCUUUGGUGCUCCUCAGGCAGGUGGAGGAAGUUUCAGGCACCUGGCUCCUCAGGUGUCUGCCAUUCAGGUGCUCUUCAGGCCUGCCCAGCAGGGCUCUCUUGAUCCAGCUAGAACUGGCCAGAACUGACUCACUCAGGAAUGUGUAGACUUUGGCAUCAGGGGCUGCUUUAAUUUGCACAAUUUCCAAAUACCUCUUUUUUCUUCUUUUUCUGAUGAGUCAUCUCCCUAGACUUGCAUUUUAAAGAGACAGAUAGUUAUCAGGUUCCAGAGAAGACAUGGUAGAAUGUUUAUAUCUCAAAGGCACAGUGUUGAGACUUCAGGUUUAGAUACUAUCAUUUGCCUAAACCAAAAAGGAGCGUGUAGGUAAAGUUCUAGUCAAGACAGGAUGGCCAGGAAAAACACCUUAAACCAAGGGACGGCUUGCUUUGCUGAUUUAAGCCAAUGGCUUCUUUAUCAUAAGACUUCCCAGUAAUUUAGUCCUUCCUCUCUUCCAGUGCACAGAGACAUACCCCUCCUUACAAAUAAAAAUUUUCUUUAUAGAUGUAAAUUUAUUUUACAAAAAUGUUUCAAAAUAACCAGAUGAAAAUCAUCAUUAUGCCAGAAAGACUUGUUUUUUUUUUUUUUUUUUCUCAUUAAUAGAAACGAAACAGUAAGUAUUUGUUGUAUUGACGUACUUAGGCUCAGACCUAUGUUUAACAAGAAAGCCUAAUAAUAGCACUGUGGUUAGACUCUAGCCAUCAUUUAAUUAUUUAGGAAAUAAAGGAUCAAAUACCUUUCAUUCAUCUGAUAUGAUUCUUUAAAACACAUUCCACUAAUAAGUCCCAUUUGGAACAGCUGAAAAUCUUUUAGUAAAAGCUUUUUAAAGAUGAGCUCGUGGCUUAGUGUAAAUUUCACAAGCUUAAUUAGGUCAAAUGGAAGGAACUCAGAUGAGUAGUUGCCCAAUCAGAGCCCAUUAUUUGUAAGUCAUCAACCCCCUUCAUGACCUAAAAACUCUACUCUGACCUAGUUAUUGCAAACCUAUAUACAACAAAGUGAAAGGAUUAAUUUUCAUUCAUCAACCUCUCAAUCCUAGAUUUUCAAAGAAAAAACCUAUCUAAGGAAUACUUACAAAAAUCAGACAGGAAAAUUAGAGCCUGCAUACUUAAGAGUCAAAUUUGUUCCACUACAGCCAGGUCGCAUACAAUUACAUCAUUUGGUUCUUCGUACACGCUAGAACUGACCAGGACAGAGUUUAGCGUAGAAAAACUGUAAGAAAUAGGUUCCUACACAUAGGAAUUGCAAAGUUCAAAAGGGUAUGAAGAAAACUAAUAUAAAUGAGAGACUCCCCUCCGUUUUAAAGAAAUACACGCUCUCUAAAAAUAUACGCAAUUUUUACAAAUACAUUUAUAAGUUGUUUUUAUCUUAAAAAUUGGGGAUAUUUCACAUUUAUAACUAAUUAUUGAGACUUAAGUUUUCUUGGCCAUUUCUAGGCUAAUAAACUAAGAAUCAUUUAAACUAAGCCAAAGUAGAAUAGAUAUAAAAGUCCUGAACACUUCAACUUCCUACUCUUCAAGAAGUAUACCCGGCAAAGCUCAUUUGAGAGAGGAAAUGCUUUCCUCCACCCUCUGUUUUACAGCGCUGAGGCUUCUUAUCACAGUUCUAUGACUUGUAGCUUAAAUCCAUGUUACAUGGUCACUGACAUUGUUGGUGCUUCUCUUUUAACACUGUAGGAAUUAAUUCGGUGGCAUAUUUAAUUAAUUUUAUCACUAGCCUGGCUGCUGGCCACCCUUCUCAACAAGGAAAUUAAGUCAGAAAGGCUUAUUUUCACUAAGUAAGACUUCGGGAACAUGGCAAAGUUCAUGACAAUAAGAAAGAAGUGGCAGCAAGGGUUGGAAAAGAGUGGUUUCAGUCAACUGAGAGGUUCCCAUGGGAGAAGCAGGAUCAAAGAGAGAGAGAGAGAAAACAGGGAGGGCUGAUUAGAUUAGUCGAUAGUUGUCCCAAGAGUGAUGCCUUUGAGGGCUUCCCUUAGUGGGGAAACAGUCCAGGCCAAAGGGAUGACCCGUGAGAUGGCUGCUGUAAAAGUGGACAAUUCUUUUUCCAGUGGCCUGGCUAUUUGCAAAAAAGGCAGACAUCUUAGGGCACAGGGGUGUUUAGUUUGCAUGCACAAGUACAAGUACUCUCAAUCCCUGCAGUUGUUGUAACUGGGAAGACACGCACCUAUUUACCUUUGUAAGGGUUUCCCCACUGUCACCACUGUAACUCUAGGUUAUCUUGAGGGAGGCCAAACUUAUCUAUCUACUGAACCCAGUCCAGUUUCCAUCUGAUCAUCAGACUGAGUGGCCUCCUACCUCGAUCCAAUGCAGUUCACAAUCAAAUCCAAUUUGAUGCUGGACUCAGUCAAGUUUUUGCCAAUGACUCGUCAGCUACCCAAACCUCAAAAGGCCGUAUAUUAUCUCACAGCAGAAACUGGCCAUUGGCACCCAUCCCAAGAUAAUUUGCCCUCUCACAGCACAAAACCCUGGAUUUGAAACCCAAAAGGAUCAAGGUUCAAUGCAAAAAGAACAGAGUCUGGCCUAAGAGGAAUGUACAACCUCAGAAGGAGGGCAAAGGGGCCAGCAGUGUCUUUCCUGCUUUCCUCAAGGGGUCUUGGGAGGUGGAUCCCAUUCAGCUUGCCAGAACUCUCAAAAGACAAAAUUACAACAAAUUUAGUUUAAAGAUCUUAUUUAGCUUUUAUUUAUUAUUUCAGAAUCAACUUUGAAACCCAGUCUGGAUAAAAAAAUUGGCUUAAACAAAUGCAUAGCUCAAAACACAAAUUCUUGGAGCUUCAAAAUUUGAGAGAGAACUUGCCCAGGACCCCUGCUGCUGUGAGAGAUCUGUGUGCACAAUGGGCCUGGUGGGUCGCUGUGCUUGGCCACUCCAUGCUUCUGGGGUUUGAUGGAAGUUCUACUUCAGAUUGCAUUUCCUACACGAAUCUGUUAAAAAAAAAAAAAAAAACCUUUACAUACAUUAAAUUUAGCAGAGUUUAUUUGAGCAAAGAAACAAUUUAGGAAUCAGGCAUCAGUUUGCACCAAAAAUGGCUCAGAACACUCCAUGCCACCGUAUGUGCAGGUUAUAUUUACAGCUAGAGAAAAAGAAGUGCACGGAAACAGCCUGAUUGGCUGCUGUUGGCAUUUACCUUAUAUAGUCAUGUUUUGGCAGCUUUCAGCCUCUGAUUGGCUGAAGGCUCAGCUGUUUUCAUUGGCUGAGACAUAGUUACAUGUUAUAAGACUACAGUCUUGGGUUAAGUUAGUUAUUUUUACACAUUAAGUUAGGUUUCAACUAGCUAUGUAUAGAGAACUCAUUAGGCCAAACUUAAAAUAAGUAUGGAGGCAGCUUUAGGACAAAGAUAAUUCAAUUUAACAAUACCCUUAUGUAUAUUUUACGCUUUUUAUGUAUUUCUAUAUAUAUUAAUAAAUAUAAGUAGUUGUAUGUACAUAUAUAAAAACAUACCUAUGUGUGUGCAUACACAUGUAUGUGAGUAUAUAUGUUUGCUUCUACCUUGUAUGAGCAAAGUAUGCCAGAGUGGCAGAGUGCUACAUAUAUAUGUGUAAAUUUCUAUAUUAAAUAUAUUUAUGUAUGUUACCUAUAUAUUUAUAUGCUCAUAAAUAUAUGUUUCCUUGAAUAGUCACCUAUGUUCUAUAUUUCUAAAUUUAUAAAUAUGCAUAUUUAUGUGUGUGUAUAUGUACAUAUAUUUAUAUUUAAUUUUUAUGUGUUGCUUCUGCCUUAUUUGUUAAGGUAGCCCAAAAUGGCAGAGAGAUUACAUAUGUAUGCUAUAAAUGUUUAUACUAUAUAUAUUAUGUUUAUGUAUAUAUUUAUAUAUGUUACGUAGUUCUUUUUUUCAAGAAUUUGAAAAAGUUUCUAAAUUGAGGAAAAAUUUACAUAAGAUUAAGCACUUUAAAGUGUAUCAUUUGGUGACAUUUAGGACAUUCUUAACACUCUCUAGUUCCAGAAUUUUUUUUCUUUUUUGAGAGGGGUCUCAUUCUGUCCCUUAUGCUGGAGUGUGGUGAUGAGAUUUUGACUCACUGCAAUCUCCACCUCCCAGGCUCAAACAAUCUUCCCACCUCAGCCUUCUGAAUAGCUGGGACCACAGGCACGUGUGCCACCACGCCCAGCUAAUUCUUCGUAUUUUUUUUGGUAAACGUGGGGUUUCACCAUGUUGCCCAGGCUGGUCUUGAACUCCUUAGCUCAGGUGAUCCACCUGCCUUGGCCUCCCAAAGUGCUGGGAGUUUUUAUAGUUCGAAGUCUUACAUUUAAGUCUUUAAUCCCUCUUGAGUUAAUUUUUGUAUAUGGUGAUAAGUAGGGGUCUAGUUUCAUUCUGGCAUCUAGAUAGCCAGUUAUCCUGGAAUCAUUUAUUGAAUAGGAAGCCCUUUUCCUAUUGCUUAUUUUUGUCACCUUUGCCAAAGAUCAGUUAGUUGUAGACGUGUGGCUUCAUUUCUGGGUUCUUUAUCCUUUUCUAAUGGUCUAUGUGUCUGUUUUUGUACCAAUACCAUGCUGUUUUGGUUACUGUAGCCUUGUAGUAUAGUUUGAAGUGAGGUAGUGUGAUGCCUCCCGCUUUGUUCUUUUUGCUUAGGAUUGCUUUGGUGAUUUGUGCUCCUUUUUAGUUCCUUAUAAAUUUUAGAAUAGGUUUUUUUUCUAAUUCUGUGAAAAAUGACAUUGGUAGUUUGAUAGGAAUAACAUUGAAUCUAGAGAUUGCUUUUGAUAGUAUGUGGCAAUUUUAACAAUAUUGAUUCUUUCUAUCCUUGAGCAUGGAGUGUUUUUCGAUUUGUUUGGGUCAGCUCUGAUUUCUUUCAGCAGUGCUUUGUAAUUCUUGUUUUCUUGUUGUAGAGAUCUUUCACCUCCCUGGUUCCCUUUAUUCCUUGGUAUUUGUGUGUGUGUGUGUGUGUGUGUGUGUGUGUGUGUGUGUCUAUUGUGAAUUAAAUGGCAUUCUUGAUUUGGCACUCAGCUUGGAUAUUGUUGGUGUAUAGAAAUACUGCUGAUUUGUGUACCUUGAUUUUGUAUCCUGAAACUUUGCUGAAGUUGUUUAUUAGAUCUAGGAGCUUUUAGGCAGAGACUAUGGGGUUUUCUAGGUAUAAAAUCAUGUUAUCUGCAAACAGAGAUAGUUUGACUUCCUGUCUUCCUAUUUGGAUGCCUUUACUUCUUUCUCUUGCCUGAUUGUCCUGGCUAGGAUUUCUAGUACUGUGUUAAAUAGGAGUGAUGGGAGUGGGUAUCCUUGUCUUGUUCCACUUCUCAAGGGGAAUGAUCCCAGCUUCUGCCUGUUCAGUGUGAUGUUGGCCGUGGGUUUGUCAUAAAUGGCUCUCAUUAUUUUGAGGUAUGUUCCCUCAAUACCUAGUUUAUUAAGGGUUUUUAACAUAAAGGGAUGUUGAAUUUUAUCAAAAGUCUUUUUUGCAUCUAUUGAGAUGAUUAUGUGGUUUUUGUUUUCAGUUCUGUUUAUGUGAUAAGUCACAUUUAUUGAUUUGCAUAUGUUGAACCAACCUUGCAUCCCAGGCAUAAACCCUGCUUGAUUAUGGUGGAUUAGCUUUUUGAUGUGCUGGUAGAUUCAGUUUGCUAGUAUUUUGUUGAGGAUUUUUGCAUCUGUGUUCAUCAAGGAUAUUGGCCUGUAGUUUUUUCUUUGCUGUGUCUCUGCCAGGCUUUGGUAUCAGAAUGAUGCUUGCCUCAUAGAAUGAGUUAGUGAGGAGUCUCUGGUCCUCAAUUGUUUGGAAUAGUUUCAAGCAGGGAUGGUAGCAGCUCUUCUUUAUACGUCUGGUAGAAUUUGGCUGUGAAUUCAUCUGAUCCUGGGCUUUUUCUUGCUCAAAAUCAUAAAAUUAGAUGGAAAUUAUUUUAUUACUGAUUCAAUUUCAAAACUCAUUAUUAGUCUGUUCAGGGUUUCAGUUUCUUCCUGGUUCAAUUUUGGGGAGUUGUGUUUUCAGGAAUUUUUCCACAUUUUGUAGGUUUUCUAGUUUGUGUGCCUAGAGGUGUUCAUAAUGGUCUCAGAGUUUUUGUAUUUCUGUAGGGUCAUUGAUAAUGUCUCCUUUGUCAAUUUUGAUUGUGUUUAUUUGGAUUUUCUCUUUCUUCUGCUGUUAGUCUAGUUAGCGUUCUAGCUAUCUUAUUUAGUCUUUAAAAAAAACUUCUGGUUUUAUUGAUCUUUUGUAUGUUUUUUCAUGCAUCACUUUAUUUCAGUUCGGCUCUGAUUUCAGUUAUUUCUUGUCUUCUUCUAGUUUUAGGGUUGGUUUGAUCUUGUUUUUCUAGUUCUUCUAGGUGUGAUGCUAUGUUGUUAAUUGGAGAUCUUUCUAACUUUUUGACAUGAGCAUUUAAUGCUAUAAACUUUCCUCUUAACAGUGCUUUAGCUGUGUCACACAGAUUCUGGUAUGUCUUAUCUUUUUUUUCUUUGGUUUUGAAGCUUUAUUUCUGCCUUAAUUUCAUAAUUUACCUAGCAGUCAUUCAAGAGCAGGUUGUUCAAUUUCCAUGUAAUUUUAUGGUUUUGAGCAAUCUUCUUAGUAUUUGCUUCUAUUUUUAUUGUGCUGUGGUUUGAGAGUGUAAUUGGUAUGAUUUCAAUUUUUAAAAAUUUUUUGAGAAUUGUUUUUUGUCUGAUUGUGUGGUCAGUUUUAGAGUAUGCACCACGUGGUGAUGAGAAUAAUAUAUAUUCUGUUGUUUUGGGGUGGGGAAUUCUGUAGAUGUCUGUUAGUUCCAUUUGGUCAAGUGUUGAGUUCAGGUCAUAUAUUUUUUAGUUUUCUGCCUUGAUGAUCUGUCUAAUACUGUCAGUGGAGGGUUGAAGUCUCCCACUAUGAUUGUGUGGAAAUUUAAGUCUCCUCACAGGUCUCUAAGAACUUGUUUUUAUGAAUCUGGGUGCUCCCUGGGUGCACACAUAAUUCUUGUGUUGGAUGCAUAUAUAUUUAGAAGAGUUAAGUCUUCUUGUUGAAUUGAACACUUUACCAUUAUGUAAUGCCCUUCUUUGUAUUUUUUGAUUGUUGUUGACUUAAAGUCUGUUUUGUCUGAAAUUAGAAUAGCAGCCCCUGCUAAUUUUUUGUUUGUUUGUUUUGUUUUUGUUUUCUGUUUACUUGGUAGAUUUUCCUCCAUCCCGUUACUUUGAGCCUAUCUGUGUCAUUGCAUGUGUGAGAUGGGUCUCUUGAAGAUGGCAUACAGUUGGGUCUUGUUUGUUUGUUUGUUUGUUUUUAAUUUUUUGAGACCGUUCUGUCUCUUUCACCCAUGCUGGAAUGCAGUGGCACAAUUAUGGCUUACUGAAGCCUCAAUCUCCUGAGUUCAGGUGAUCUUUACACUUCAACUUCUGGAGUAGCUGGGACUACAAGUGCAGGCCACCGUGCCUAACUAAUUUUAUAUUUUUUAUAGAGAUGAGUUUUUCCCAUGUUGCCCAGGCUGGUCUCGAACACCUGGGCUUAAGCGAUCUGCCCACCUUGGUCUCCCAAAGUGCUGGGAUUACAGACAUGAGCCAUUGCACCCAAGUGGGUCUCGCUUCUUUAUUCAACUUGCCACUCUGUGCAUUUCAAUUGGGGCAUUUAGCCCACUUACAUUCAAAGUUAAUAAUUCUAUGUAUGGAAUUGAUCCUGUCCUUAUAUAUAUAUAUUUUUAGCUGGUUAUUAUGCAGACUAGACUUGAUUUUGUAGUUGCUUUGUAGCAUUAAUGGUCUAUGUAUUUAAGUGUGUUUUUGUGAUGACUGGUAAUGGUCUUUUGUUUUCAUAUUUAUUUUAUUUUAUUUUGAGACAGGAUCUCACUCUGCUGCCCAGGCAGAGUGCAAUGGUAUGAUCUGGGCUCACUGCAACCUCUGCUUCCUGGGCUCAAGCCAUCCUCCUGCCUUAGUCUCCUGAGUGGUUGGGACCACAGGCGCAUACCACCAUUCCUAGCUGAUUUUUAUAUUUUUUUGUAGAGACAGGGUUUCACCAUGUUGCCCAGUCUGGUUUUGAACUCCUGGGCUCAAGUGAUCCGCCUGCCUCAGCCUCCUGAAGUGCUAGGAUUACAGGCGUGAGCCACUGCGCCUGGCUUGUUUCUAUAUUUAACACUCCCUUAGAGACCUCUUUUAAGGCAGGUCUGGUGGUGAUAAAUUCCCUUAACAUUUGCUUGUCUGAAAAGUAUCUUCUCCUUUGCUUAUGAAGUUUGUUUGACUGUAUAUGAAAUUUUUGGGCUCCCCGGCAUUGCGCCAUCAAAAACAAAGUCGUUCUCCAACUUCUUGUCCUGCAUCACUGCCAUCGCAGCUCUCAGCACUAAAAAGGUGGCAUCAGACUCCUCCAAAGAACAAGUGGCCAAUUCGAGGGAAUCCUCCUCGUUAUCAAAAGAAGUAAACGACAGUCCGAGAGCCGCCGACAAGUCUCCUGAAUCCCAGAAUCUCAUCGACGGGACCAAAAAAACAUCCCUAAAGCAACUGGAUAGUCCCAGAAACAUCUCAAGUGAGAACAGCAUCAAAGGAACCCCGGCUUCUCCCGCAGGGUCCACACCACCAAUCCCCAAAGUCCGCAUAAAAACCACUAAGACGUCUUCUGGGGAAAUCAAGAGAACAGUGACCAGGGUAUUGCCAGAAGUGGAUCUUGACUCUGGGAAGAAACCUUCCGAGCAGACGGUGUCUGUGAUGGCCUCUGUGACAUCCCUUCUGUCGUCUCCCGCAUCAGCUGCCACCCUUUCCUCUCCCGCCAGGGUGCCUCUCCAGUCUGCAGUGGUGACCAAUGCAGUUUCCUCUGCAGAGCCCACCCCUAAACAGGUCACAAUCAAGCCUGUGGCUACUGCUUUCCUCCCAGUGUCUGCUGUGAAGACAGCAGGAUCCCAAGUCAUUAAUUUGAAGCUCGCUAACAACACCACGGUGAAAGCCACGGUCGUACCUGCUGCCUCUGUCCAGAGUGCCAGCAGCACCAUCAUUAAAGCUGCCAAUGCCAUCCAGCAGCAAACUGUCAUGAUGCCAGCAUCCAGCCUGGCCAAUGCCAAACUUGUGCCAAAGACUGCAUCUUGCCAACCUUAACCUUCUGCCUCAGGUUGCCCAGGCCACCUCUGAACUCUGCCAAGUGUCAAUCAAAACUCAGCAACAGAUAAAGAAGGCAAUAAUUAAUGCAGCAGCCUCACAAGCCCCCAGAAAGGUGUCUCGAGUCCGGGUGGUGUCGUCCUUGCAGAGUUCUGUGGUGGAAACUUUCAACAAGGUGCUGAGCAGUGUCAAUCCAGUCCAUUUACAUCCCAAACCUCAGUCCUCCUGCCAAUGCAGGGAUCACAUUACUGAUGCCUUGGUACAAGUGCUUGGAGUGUAGGGACUCCUUUGAACUUGAAAAGAGUCUGACCCAGCACUAUGACAGAUGGAGCGUGUGCAUCGAAGUAACAUGCAACCUUUGUACAAAGAACCUCGUUUUUUUACAACAAAUGCAGCCUCCUUUCCCAUGCCCGUGGGCAUAAGGAGAAAGGGGUGGUAAUGCAAUGUUCCUACUCAAUUUUAAAGCCAGUCCCAGCAGGUCAAACGAUAGUUUCUCCAUCAACCAAUACUUCUUCUUCAUCAGAGGAAAAAUCCACUCUUCAGAGCCCUGUGGGAGCUGGCAUACACACUGUCACAAAAAUUCAGUCUGGCAUAACUGGGACAGUCAUAUCGGCUCCUUCAAGAACUCCCAGCACUACAGCCAUGCCCCUAGAUGAAGACCCCUCCAAGCUGUGUAGACAUAAUCUAAAAUGUUUGGAGUGUAAUGAAAUCUUCCAGGACAAGACAUCGCUGGCUACACAUUUCCAGCAGGCUGCAGAUAUGAGUGGACAAAAGACUUGUACUAUCUGCCAGAUGCUGCUUCCUAACCAGUGCAGAGAAUCCAUCAGCACAAAUCUCCUUAAACCUGCCCUGAGUGCAGGGCCAUCUGCAGGUUGGUGCACUUCCAGACCCACGUCACCAAGAACUGUCUGCACUACACAAGGAGAGUUGGUUUUUGAUGUGUACGUUGCAAUGUUGUGUACUCUGAUGUGGCUGCUCUGAAGUCUCGCCUUCAAGGUUCUCACUGUGAAGUCUUCUACAAGUGUCCUAUUUGUCCAAUGACGUUUAAGUCUGCCCCAAGCACACAUUCCCACACCUACACACAGCAUCCUAGCAUCAAGAUAGGAGAAUCAAAAAUAAUAUAUAAGUGUUCCAUGUGCAACACUGUGUUCACCCUGCAAACCUUGCUGUAUCGCCACUUUGACCAACACAUUGAAAACCAGAAGGUGUCUGUUCUCAGGUGUCCAGACUGUUCUCUUUUAUAUGCACAGAAGCAACUUAUGGUGGACCAUAUCAAGUCUAUGCAUGGGACAUUGCAAAGCAUUGAAGGGCCAACUUGGGUGUAAACUUGCCUUUGAGCAUUAAGCCUGCAACUUAUAAUUCAGCAUAUCAGAACAAAGAGGACAGCAAAUCCAUGAAUGGGAAAGAGAAAUUGGAAAAGAAAUCUCCAUCUCCUUUGAAAAAAAUCAGUGGAAACCAAGAAAGUGGCCAGUCCUGGGUGGACAUGUUGGGAGUGUGACCGCCUGUUCAUGCAGAGAGAUGUGUACAUAUCCCACGUCAGGAAGGAGCAUGGGAAACAAAUGAAGAAACAACCCUGCUGCCAGCGUGACAAGCCUUUCAGCUCGUCCCACAGCCUGUGCUGGCACAACCGGAUCAAGCACAAAGUCAUCAGGAAAGUGUACACCUGUUCACACUGCUCAGACUCUAGAGGUACCUUUACCAAACAGUUGAUGUUGGAGAAGCAUGUCCAGCUGACGCAUGGCAUCAAGGACCCUGACCUGAAAGAAAUGAUAGACGCCAUCAAUGAGGAGGAAACAGAAAUAAAAGAAGACCCCAAGGUCCCCAGUCCCAAGUGGAAGUUGAAAGAACCGGUUCUGGAGUUCAGGCCUCCCAGAGGAGCAAUCACUCAACCAAAGCUGGAAAUCAAUGUUUUUAAGGUUCACAAGUGUGCCGUGUGUGGCUUCACCACCGAAAACCUGCUGCAGUUCCACGAACACAUCCCUCAGCACAAAUCGGAUGGUUCUUUCUACCAGUGCCGGGAGUGUGGCCUCUGCUACAUGUCACGUCUCUCUGUCCAGGCACCUCUUUGUUGUACACAAGUUAAAGGAACCUCAGCCAGUGUCCAAGCAAAACGGGGCUGGGGAAGAUAACCAACAGGAGAACAAACCCAGUCACGAGGAUGAAUCUCCCAAUGGCGCCAUGUCAGACAGAAAGUGCAAAGUGUGCGCAAAAACUUUUGAAACUGAAGCUGCCUUAAAAACUCACAUGCAGACACAUGGUAUGGCCUUCAUCAAAUCCAAAAGGAUGAGCUCAGACGAGAAAUAGCCACAGACGCUCCAUGAGGAAAAUCCCUGUCCACAUUGGCAUAAGACACUUUUGUUACACAAAGUUUGCAGUAUAAUAGAGUUAACAAUACUGUCUAGGCUGUUGCAAUAUAUUCUCUUUCAACGUGCCUUCCUUCUUCAUCUUGUCAUAUAUAUCCUCAUUAAGUAUUAAAACAGAUUUUGAGUUUAAAAGAGUUUGUAUAUAUUUAAAUGAAUAACUUUUUAUACUCUUUGUUACAUGUUUGUAUCAGUAUUCAGUGGAAAACGUUUUGAGUUGUUUUGGGUUAGAAUUUUUCUUUUUGUGCUGUUUCUUUAAAACAGAGUUCUUAGUAACAGGGGCAGUUCCUGAAUUCAAAUAAAUCAUUUUGUAUGUUUCGAAUUUGAAUGGGUUAACUAAUUACAGGCUAAAAUAAUGCCUUUUUUAGUGUUUUUAAUUGUUAGAAUUCACUACAUAAAUUGGAAGUAAUCGUGGGUCUCAAAAACACUAGGAACUUUUAAAUGUCUUAGCACCUCCUCCAUGUGCCUGCCCUGAGGGAGCGAGUACACGUUUGAGACAACUGCACUCCAGUGUGGGCAUGUCUUUGUCUUCAGGCCACGCCGAAGGGUGUCUAAAGCAGCCUUGCAGGUCGCUCCUUUCCCAGCCGUGGAUAAAAACUGAAGCCAGGAAUCUAAUAAGGAAUGCUGAUUUCCUCAAUUCCAUUUUGAGGAAUGGGGAAGGCUAUUCUAAAGAAGAAAAAAAAUGGGACAGGUUUUCUGGGUAGAUCUGCAAGUCUGGCUUUAAGAGCACAAGGAGGAAAAGUAACAAAAGGGCUGGACUACUGUAAAAGUUACAAAUACGUAGUUAGACCAAUAGAUCUAUAUAGUCAGGUUUUUGUCAUGUAAUUUAUUAACUAUUACAGAAACACAACUAAGAAUAUCAAGUAUUUCUCUGGCUCUUGAUAGAAAAAAAAAUCAGCUGACUUAAUCCUUUACUGUCAAAAGAGUUGGCGUUUCCUGUUCUGGGUGCUACUGCCAAACGUUCUGGUGCUUAGAGGUGGGAUGCACGACGUCAACCACCGACUUAUCAAUGCAGCCGGCUGUGUGUCACAAUUGGCCGUUACCUUAAGCACUGAGCCACACGGGAUUAGUUCAGCCAUUUCAAGAGGUACAUUUAACGUCGGCAGUUCUGCUUUACUAAAAUGCAGUAGAGGUACUCUUCUGUCCCUUCCGUUUAUAGUUCUCUGAGAGAGUUAUAUUUUUUGGUUUUGUUUUGUGUUUUCUUUUGAAUUUUAUAUCUUGUAUUUAUCCCUGAACAUGUUUUGUACUUUUUUUUUUAAGAAAAGGAAUUAUUUUGUGUAUAUAUAGACACUUGCAUGAUAUACUGUAGUCAAUGUUCGGUUCCUCGAAAGGUCUUGCUGCUGUCAGGUGUUAUACACUCCAUCCAUCAUAACUGUAUGAAACACAUUUCAUAUGUAAAUAAACGUGGGACAUUUGAAAAAAA